GACUAGGAGCUGGCGGUCCGAGCUGUGGCUUGGAAGACCGACGCGAUGAAGCCCAGACCUGCAGGGUUCGUGGAUAAUAAACUCAAGCAGCGAGUCAUCCAGUACCUUACCAGUAACAAAUGUGGCAAAUAUGUGGACAUUGGAGUCUUAGCGUCUGAUUUACAAAGAGUGUACAGUAUAGACUAUGGUCGAAGAAAAAGAAAUGCUUUUAGGAUUCAGGUAGAAAAAGUAUUUAGCAUAAUUAGUAGUGAGAAGGAACUUAAGAAUUUAACAGAAUUAGAAGAUGAACAUUUGGCAAAAAGGGCAAGACAAGGUGAAGAGGAUAAUGACGUCUCGCUCUGUCACCCAGGCUUCAGUGCACUGGCACAAUCAUGGCUUACCGCAGUCUUGACGUCCCAGGCCCAAGCGAUCCUCCCACCGCAGCCUCACAGGUAUACUGAAAGCUAUUCUGAUGAUGAUUCAAGUAUGGAAGACUACCCAGAUCCACAGUCAGCAAAUCACAUGAACAGUUCCCUGCUGUCUUUAUAUCGGAAAGGAAAUCCUGAUUCUGUUUCAAAUACUCCUGAGAUGGAGCAAAGAGAAACCACCUCUUCAACACCACGGAUAAGUUCCAAAACAGGCUCCAUUCCCUUGAAGACCCCUGCCAAAGAUUCUGAAGGAGGAUGGUUUAUUGACAAAACCCCAAGUGUAAAGAAAGACAGUUUUUUCUUGGACCUGUCAUGUGAGAAAAGUAAUCCUAAGAAGCCAAUAACUGAGAUACAGGAUUCAAAAGAUUCUUCUCUUUUGGAGAGUGAUAUGAAACGGAAAGGCAAGCUAAAGAAUAAAGGAAGCAAAAGGAAGAAAGAAGAUCUUCAGGAAGUAGAUGGAGAAAUUGAAGCUGUCCUGCAAAAGAAAGCUAAAGCCAGGGGGUUAGAAUUCCAGAUCUCCAACGUGAAGUUUGAAGAUGUGGGAGGCAAUGAUAUGACAUUAAAAGAGGUCUGCAAGAUGCUCAUACACAUGCGUCACCCGGAGGUGUACCACCACCUGGGCGUCGUGCCCCCUCGUGGAGUUCUCCUUCAUGGACCACCAGGCUGUGGGAAGACAUUACUUGCACAUGCAAUUGCUGGGGCUGAGUGCAGUGGCAUGAUCACAGCUCACUGCAGCUUUGACUUCUCAGGCUCAAAUGAUCCUCCUGCCUCAGCCUCACAGGAACUUGACCUGCCAAUUUUGAAAGUGGCUGCUCCAGAGAUUGUGUCUGGAGUAUCCGGAGAGUCUGAGCAGAAGCUGAGAGAACUAUUUGAGCAAGCUGUGUCAAAUGCACCAUGUAUCAUUUUCAUUGAUGAAAUUGAUGCUAUUACCCCCAAAAGAGAAGUGGCUUCAAAAGAUAUGGAACGAAGAAUUGUAGCCCAACUCCUAACCUGCAUGGAUGAUCUGAAUAAUGUGGCUGCUACAGCCCGGGUCCUAGUUAUUGGAGCUACUAAUCGACCAGACUCGUUAGACCCUGCUUUGAGACGUGCGGGAAGGUUCGACCGAGAAAUAUGCCUAGGUAUCCCAGAUGAAGCAUCCAGGGAAAGAAUACUUCAAACAUUGUGCAGAAAACUGAGGCUUCCUCAAGCUUUUGAUUUCUGUCACUUAGCACACCUAACUCCAGGCUUUGUUGGUGCUGAUCUCAUGGCACUGUGCCGAGAGGCAGCAAUGUGUGCAGUCAAUAGAGUCUUAAUGAAGCUACAGGAACAGCAGAAGAAAAAUCCUGAAAUGGAAGAUUUGCCAUCUAAAGGAGUCCAGGAGGAAAGGCUGGGAACUGAGCCCACUUCUGAAACACAGGAUGAAUUACAAAGGCUGCUGGGGUUGCUAAGAGACCAAGAUCCCCUCUCAGAGGAGCAGAUGCAAGGACUGUGCAUUGAACUGAAUGAUUUCAUUGUUGCUCUAUCCUCAGUCCAACCCUCUGCCAAAAGGGAAGGCUUUGUCACUGUCCCUAAUGUGACAUGGGCAGAUAUUGGUGCCCUGGAAGACAUUAGAGAGGAGCUCACCAUGGCAAUAUUGGCACCAGUACGCAACCCAGACCAGUUCAAAGCUCUUGGAUUGGUGACUCCAGCUGGGGUCCUCCUUGCUGGUCCUCCUGGCUGUGGGAAGACUCUGCUGGCGAAGGCUGUUGCAAAUGAGUCCGGACUAAAUUUUAUAUCUGUCAAGGGCCCCGAAUUACUAAACAUGUAUGUUGGUGAGAGUGAACGUGCUGUGCGACAAGUUUUUCAACGAGCCAAGAACUCAGCACCCUGUGUGAUAUUCUUUGAUGAAGUGGAUGCUUUAUGUCCUCGAAGAUCAGACCGAGAGGAAUAAAGAAUGGCUGCUCCAUAGGCAGAGCAGCCUUAUCUGUUUCUUGGAUGUCUACUGCCGUACAUUUCUUUUUUUUUUUUUCUUUUGAGAGAGAGUCUUGCUCUGUCACCCAGGCUGGAGUGCAAUGGCACUAUCUCAGCUCACUGCAACCUCUGCCUCCCAGGUUCAAGCGAUUUUCCUGACUCAGCCUCCCGAGUAGCUGAGAUUACAGGCGCCUGCUACCAUGCCCAGCUAAUAUUUGUAUUUUCAGUAGAGAUGGGGUUUCACCAUGAUGGCCGGGCUGGUCUCGAACUCUUGGUCUCAAGUGAUCCACCAUCCUCGGCCUCCCAAAGUACUGGGAUUAGAGGCGUGAGCCACCACGCCCAGCCUACUGCCAUACAUUUCUAUACUCUGAUAUAUAUGGUUUUCUUUUCUUGUGUUUUUGUUGUGUUUUUUUUUGUUUGUUUGUUUUUUUUGUUUUUUUUUGAGACGGAGUCUCGCUCUGUCGCCCAGGCUGGAGUGCAGUGGCGGGAUCUCGGCUCACUGCAAGCUCCGCCUCCCGGGUUCACGCCAUUCUCCUGCCUCAGCCUCCCAAGUAGCUGGGACUACAGGCGCCCGCCACUACGCCCGGCUAAUUUUUUGUAUUUUUAGUAGAGACGGGGUUUCACCGUUUUAGUCGGGAUGGUCUCGAUCUCCUGACCUCGCGAUCCGCCCGCCUCGGCCUCCCAAAGUGCUGGGAUUACAGGCAUGAGCCACCGCGCACGGCCUGUUGUGUUUUGUUUUUUGUUUUGUUUGUUUGUUUUGAGACAGAGUCUUGCUCUGUCACCCAAGCUGGAGUGCAGUGGUGUAAUCUCAGCUCACUGCAGCCUCUGCCUCCCAGGUUCAAGCGAUUUUCCUGACUCAGCCUCCCAAGUAGCUGGGACUACAGAUGUGUGCCACCACACCUGGCUAAUUUUGUAUUUUUAGUAGAGACGGGGUUUUACCACUUUGGCCAGGCUGGUCUUGAACUCCUGACCUCAGGUGAUCCACUCGCCUUGGCCUCCCAAAGUGCUGGCAUUACAGAUGUGAGCCACUACGCCCAGCUAUAGUUUGCUUUUCUAACAUUUUCACCUAAAGCAGAUUCUAAAAACAUUUUAUUUUUAUUUUUUGUUUCUUUUUAUUUGAUUUUUUUUUUUUUAAAACAGAGUCUCACUCUCACUCAAGCUGGAGUGCAGUGGCGCGAUCUCAGCUCUUCGCAACUUCUGCCUCCUGGGUUCAAGCGAUUCUUGUGCCUCAGCCUCCUGAGUAGCUGGGACUACAGGUGUGUGCCACCAUGCCCAGCUGAUUUUUUGUAUUUUUUUUUUUUUAGUAGAGACAGGGUUUCACCAUGUUGGCCAGGCUGGUCUCGAACUUCUAACCUCAGGUGAUCCACCUGCCUCAGCCUUCCAAAGUGCUAGGAUUACAGGCAUGAGCCACCAUGCCUGGCCUCUAAAAACAUUUUAAAUUUGAAUGCAUUCUGUUUUUUUUGAGACAGAGUCUCGUUCUGUUGCCCAGGCUGGAGUGCAGUGGCGCAAUCUCGGCUCACUGCAACCUCUGCCUCCUGGGUUCAUGCGAUUCUCCUGCCUCAGCCUCCCGAGUAGCUGGGAUUACAGGCGCACACCACCACGCCUGGCUAAUUUUUUGUGUAUUUUUAGUAGAGAUGGGGUUUCACUAUGUUGGCCAGACUGGUCUCGAACUCCUGACCUCGUGAUCUGCCCGCCUCGGCCUCCUAAAGUGUUGAGAUUACAGGCGUGAGCCACCGCGCCUGGCAAAUGUAUUCUUUUUUAAUUGCACUAGUUAUACAUGAAUACACAUUUGUGAAAAAUUCAAAUAAAACACAAGUAUAAAGAGAGUAAA